GCACUCUCCCGGACUGCCACGCACAGCGCGCUGCGGGGCCGCGUGCACCGGCGGUCGGGCGGAGGCCGCGCUCCUGCUGGCUCCGCGCUCCGUCCCGGCCGCAGCUCGGGGCCUGCAGGGGCAGUCCCGGGUGCCCGCCGGCCGCGCCGCCCUUCCGGGCCCUGGCCGUCCACCCGCGCUCCCACGCGGGCUCGCCGCCUUCGCGCUCCCGCUCGGGGAGUCCCCGGGCUGCCGGGCGCGGGCGGACCCCCCAUGGGACGAGGGUUGCAGGGACUGCGGCGGAGCGAGGCGUGACCCGCGCGGCGAGCCCGGGCUGGGGGCGUGCGCCGAGCGGGGCUGCCCGCGCGACCUUUUCCUGUUCUUGCAGGCGGCUGAUGGUGAGACCAUUCUAAAAGGCCUCCAGUCCAUUUUCCAGGAGCAGGGGAUGGCGGAGUCGGUGCACACCUGGCAGGACCAUGGCUAUUUAGCAACCUACACAAACAAGAACGGCAGCUUUGCCAAUUUGAGAAUUUACCCACAUGGAUUGGUGUUGCUGGACCUUCAGAGUUAUGAUGGUGAUGCGCAAGGCAAAGAAGAGAUCGACAGUAUUUUGAACAAAGUAGAGGAAAGAAUGAAAGAAUUGAGUCAGGACAGUACUGGGCGGGUGAAACGAUUACCACCCAUAGUGCGAGGAGGAGCCAUCGACAGAUACUGGCCCACCGCCGACGGGCGCCUGGUUGAAUAUGACAUAGAUGAAGUGGUAUAUGACGAAGAUUCACCUUAUCAAAAUAUAAAAAUUCUACACUCGAAGCAGUUUGGAAAUAUUCUCAUCCUUAGUGGGGAUGUUAAUUUGGCAGAGAGUGAUUUGGCAUAUACCCGGGCCAUCAUGGGCAGUGGCAAAGAAGAUUACACUGGCAAAGAUGUACUCAUUCUGGGAGGUGGAGACGGAGGCAUAUUGUGUGAAAUAGUCAAACUAAAACCAAAGAUGGUCACUAUGGUAGAGAUUGACCAAAUGGUGAUUGAUGGGUGUAAGAAAUACAUGCGAAAAACGUGUGGCGAUGUCUUAGACAAUCUUAAAGGAGACUGCUAUCAGGUUCUAAUAGAAGACUGUAUCCCGGUACUGAAGAGGUACGCCAAAGAAGGGAGAGAAUUUGAUUAUGUGAUUAAUGAUUUGACAGCUGUUCCAAUCUCCACGUCUCCAGAAGAAGAUUCCACAUGGGAGUUUCUCAGACUGAUUCUUGACCUCUCAAUGAAAGUGUUGAAACAGGAUGGGAAAUAUUUUACACAGGGGAACUGUGUCAAUCUGACAGAAGCACUGUCGCUCUAUGAAGAACAGCUGGGGCGCCUGUAUUGUCCUGUGGAAUUUUCAAAGGAGAUCGUCUGUGUCCCUUCAUACUUGGAAUUGUGGGUAUUUUACACUGUUUGGAAGAAAGCUAAACCCUGAAGAUCAGUAGCCCCUAAUCACAUGUGCUGCAAAUAGCCUUCCUGACCUCCAUAUGCUGUACAUGACAUCAAAAUGAGUCAGGCAAUUGAUUGUGAAUUCCUUAAAGUUUUCCUUUUUUUAAUAAUUAUUUUUAAUUUAAAAAAGCAAAUGGAAAAUGUAUAUUUUGAUGAGCUUAGGGUGUUUUUUUUUUGAAAGUCAGCUGAAGGAUGGUUAGACAGCACAGCGAAGACUGCUAAAUGCACUGACCCCCCCCAUUAGAAUGUGAUUUUUGUUCCUUUUUAUUUCUCUGUGGGCUUUUGUUUUUGUUUUUGUUUUGGUAGAUCUUCAAUUUGGAUAUUUGGAGGAGUGAACAUCGUUGUUUUGCUGGAGGGAAGAUCUUGAUGGUGUUUCUUUCCCCAAAAAUUGACUUAGAUAUUAAAAUUUGGUGCUUAUAAGAGAGAGUUAAAAAAAAAUAGGAUUGCUUCAAUUAAAAUUACAAAAGAGACA